ACUGGUUGAGCCGGGUAGGGAAAGCAGCCUAAAGCCCGGGACAGGCACACAGGCCCAGGUGUGUAGGCCACAGCAGCCGCAGUCCUGAAAGGCUGCAACACCCAGACCUCCAGGAGAGACCAGGCCCAGGAUGCCUCGCCUGUUCUUGUUCCACCUGCUAGAAUUCUGUUUACUACUGAACCAAUUUUCCAGAGCAGUCGCGGCCAAAUGGAAGGACGAUGUUAUUAAAUUAUGCGGCCGCGAAUUAGUUCGCGCGCAGAUUGCCAUUUGCGGCAUGAGCACCUGGAGCAAAAGGUCUCUGAGCCAGGAAGAUGCUCCUCAGACACCUAGACCAGUGGCAGGUGAUUUUAUUCAAACAGUCUCACUGGGAAUCUCACCGGACGGAGGGAAAGCACUGAGAACAGGAAGCUGCUUCACCCGAGAGUUCCUUGGUGCCCUUUCCAAAUUGUACCAUCCUUCAUCAACAAAGAUACAGAAACUAUAAUUAUCAUGUUGGAAUUCAUUGCUAAUUUGCCACCGGAGCUGAAGGCAGCCCUAUCUGAGAGGCAACCAUCAUUACCAGAGCUACAGCAGUAUGUACCUGCAUUAAAGGAUUCCAAUCUUAGCUUUGAAGAAUUUAAGAAACUUAUUCGCAAUAGGCAAAGUGAAGCCGCAGACAGCAAUCCUUCAGAAUUAAAAUACUUAGGCUUGGAUACUCAUUCUCAAAAAAAGAGACGACCCUACGUGGCACUGUUUGAGAAAUGUUGCCUAAUUGGUUGUACCAAAAGGUCUCUUGCUAAAUAUUGCUGAGAUGAAGCUAAUUGUGCACAUCUUGUCUAAUUUUCACACAUAGUCUUGAUGACAUUUCACUGAUGCUUCUGUCAGGUCCCACUAAUUAUUAGAAUAUAAGAAAUCUUUAUUAAUGUUUAGAUUUUUCAUUUGGUGUGUAAGAAAAUAUUCUUUGUAUGAUUGUAGUUUCUGUAAAUGACACUUUCUAUGCUGAAGUCUUUUUGUCUUUUUAUUAACAGUAUAAUUGUGUUGAUUCUUUUUAAUGCUGUUAACUUAAAAUUACAAUAAAACCUUUGCCACUUUAACCAUACAUAAUAACAAUACAGUACCUAACAACAGUUA